GGAGCUGGGGCGGAGCCGCAGGGCCUGGCGGCCGCCGAGUGAAGUGUGACUCCGUGGGCCUGGCGUGGAGGCGGGGGCGCUAGGCUGCAGCUGGCUCGGAAUCGGGGCUGGUUUCCUGUCUGGAAGGGAAGGGGCCUGCAGAAGGGAGCGGGGACAGCAGCAGACAGGCACACCCCUGCCUUCCUCUCUCCCUCUCCUCCCUUCUCUGGAAAAGCGAGGUAAUUGUGAGCCCAGGGUGGAGCGGGCUGGAUGGGGGCCCUGAGUUGGAAGGGGUGGCCCUAGGGCUGGGCUGCUUUGCCAACUCACCCCUUUGUCCCAUUCCCUGGGCUCACUCUCCCCUGAGGUCCUCACCUGUGUGGCUCUUUUUCCCAACUUUCUCAAACUAAGCUGGAACCCCUCUCGGGAAGCUCCAACCUCCUGCAAACCCCAUGACUCUAGAACCUGCAUGAGGCGUCGUUUCCCUGCCCCCUUCCAGUUGUGCCUGCCCCUCACUGCCCUCUCCGCACACAGAUUCCCUGUCCACCAGGCCAGGGAUGUGGGCGGGGGCUGGGGAGCGGCCAGAGUCGGAAUGAAAGGGCCUUUUUCUUCCACAGCUGGGAGAACAGCUGCCACCAAAGCGAGACUGGACACUCUGUGCCUAGAGCCCCCUCUGCAGCUGGCCUUUCCUCCUGGGACCCCACUUAUCCUCACUUCGCUUUCUUUUUCUUCCCUGCCUGGCUCCCGGCAGGGCCCCGGAGCAGCAGUGGGCGAGGAAAAUUUGUCACAGCAGCCAGAGGGGUUUAACAGGAGUGCAGAGGGAUAAGGGCAGCUUCUGCCCUCUGCCCAAGAGCUGGCCACCUCUUUAAAGACUGAGGGAACAGUGGGAGGAGGAACUGUGGGACAGUGUGGUACCUAUCUGUCCCCCCUCUGGAGGGGUUGACAAGGGAAAGGGCACCGGGGGGCACAGAGAUGCAGGACAGAUUGCACAUCCUGGAGGACCUGAAUAUGCUCUACAUUCGGCAGAUGGCACUCAGCCUGGAGGACACGGAGUUGCAGAGGAAGCUAGACCAUGAGAUCCGGAUGAGGGAAGGGGCCUGUAAGCUGCUGGCAGCCUGCUCCCAGCGAGAGCAGGCUCUGGAGGCCACCAAGAGCCUGCUAGUGUGCAACAGCCGCAUCCUCAGCUACAUGGGCGAGCUGCAGCGGCGCAAGGAGGCGCAGGUGCUGGGGAAGACAAGCCGGCGGCCUUCUGACAGUGGCCCGCCCGCUGAGCGCUCCCCCUGCCGCGGCCGGGUCUGCAUCUCUGACCUCCGGAUUCCACUCAUGUGGAAGGACACAGAAUAUUUCAAGAACAAAGGUGACUUGCACCGCUGGGCUGUGUUCCUGCUGCUGCAGCUGGGGGAACACAUCCAGGACACAGAGAUGAUCCUAGUGGACAGGACCCUCACAGACAUCUCCUUUCAGAGCAAUGUGCUCUUCGCUGAGGCGGGGCCAGACUUUGAACUGCGGUUAGAGCUGUAUGGGGCCUGUGUGGAAGAAGAGGGGGCCCUGACUGGCGGCCCCAAGAGGCUUGCCACCAAACUCAGCAGCUCCCUGGGCCGCUCCUCAGGGAGGCGUGUCCGGGCAUCGCUGGACAGUGCUGGGGGUUCAGGGAGCAGUCCCAUCUUGCUCCCCACCCCAGUUGUUGGUGGUCCUCGUUACCACCUCUUGGCUCACACCACACUCACCCUGGCAGCAGUGCAAGAUGGAUUCCGCACACAUGACCUCACCCUUGCCAGUCAUGAGGAGAACCCUGCCUGGCUGCCCCUUUAUGGUAGCGUGUGUUGCCGUCUGGCAGCUCAGCCUCUCUGCAUGACUCAGCCCACUGCAAGUGGUACCCUCAGGGUGCAGCAAGCUGGGGAGAUGCAGAACUGGGCACAAGUGCAUGGAGUUCUGAAAGGCACAAACCUCUUCUGUUACCGGCAACCUGAGGAUGCAGACACUGGGGAAGAGCCGCUGCUUACUAUUGCUGUCAACAAGGAGACUCGAGUCCGGGCAGGGGAGCUGGACCAGGCUCUAGGACGGCCCUUCACCCUAAGCAUCAGUAACCAGUAUGGGGAUGAUGAGGUGACACACACCCUUCAGACAGAAAGUCGGGAAGCACUGCAGAGCUGGAUGGAGGCUCUGUGGCAGCUUUUCUUUGACAUGAGCCAAUGGAAGCAGUGCUGUGAUGAAAUCAUGAAAAUUGAAACUCCUGCUCCCCGGAAACCACCCCAAGCACUGGCAAAGCAGGGGUCCUUGUACCAUGAGAUGGUCUUAUCAGAGCCUGUAGCCCCAGGGGGCCCAGGUGAGGGGCUGCUCCUGCAGGAUAACGCAAUCUCCACUGAGAUCCAGGCUUUGCUUUCCUCCUAUUACAGUGACAGGUGAUAGGGCUGGGUAGGCUUGGGGCCUGAGCUCUGACUAGCCCAACCCUCCCCCAACCCCUUCCUGGUGCCACAGCUAUUGAGCCGCUGGAUGACAUCGCAGCGGUGACAGACAUCCUGACCCAGCGGGAGGGCGCAAGGCUGGAGACACCCCCACCCUGGCUGGCAAUGUUUACAGACCAGCCUGCCCUGCCUAACCCCUGCUCGCCUGCCUCAGUGGCCCCAGCCCCAGACUGGACCCACCCCCUGCCCUGGGGGAGACCCCGAACCUUUUCCCUGGAUGCUGUCCCCCCAGACCACUCCCCUAGGGCUCGCUCGGUUGCCCCCCUCCCACCUCAGCGAUCCCCACGGACCAGAGGCCUCUGCAGCAAAGGCCAACCUCGCACUUGGCUCCAGUCACCAGUGUGAGAGAGAAAGGUGCUGGCAUAGGAUCUGCCCAGAAGAGAAAAUGACCCAUGCGCAGUUGGGCUCUGGAUACGGCGCUGUCUAUAGCAAGUUGGCCAGUCUGGCCUCCUGUUCCUCUGCUGGACCUGGGGUAGGCUGCAGGGGUGGGCAGAAGCCCCUCUUAAAUUGUGGUUGCCAUGGUACCGAGGGACUCAUUCCUGGGGCUCGCUGGGACCUCCCUAAACCCUUCCUGGAAGAAAACUGGAACCAACUCUGCCCUACCUCCCUGCACUAACCAGCUUUGAGGAUGGCACUGAAGAACCCUUGGAGCAAACAUACCUCCCUUGUGACUCCCACAUCAACCAUUAAAGUUAUUUAACAGCA